UCACAGAUAUUUUAUUUUAUUUUUUGUGAUAUAAUCUAGUACUAUCACUGUUUAUUUUCUCACUCAAAUUGUUCCACCUUUGGCCACUGGGAGCUCUUUCAGUUUGCCUCCUCUACCCUUUGACAUAUCUUCAACCUUUUUUGAGCGCUUUCUUAUUUUCUAACACUGCCAGAUGUUCCAAGCUCAUCUUGUAUUUUUUUUUCUCUGUUUGCAGCCUGGAAUCAAUCACUUCUCUAAAGCAUUUCAUAGGAUGUUGAAAUUUUACAGACUUCUAACUGAAUGCACUCUCUUAAGUAUCAUAAGGUUAUCUUAAAGGUGAUAACCAAUUGCAAGAACAAUUCCUCCGUUAAUAUGUUUUACUGUUCCAAAAGAAAUCAUUUUGCUCAUUACCUUAUGUAUUUCUAUUUUUAAUUUUUAUGGAUUCAUAGAAGCUGUACAUAUUUAUGGACACGUCAUAUUUUGAUACAAAUAUACAAUGUGUAAUGAUUGAAACUGGGUAAUUGGGAUUUUUAUCACCUCAAACAUUUAUUAUUUCUUUUUGUUGUCAACAUUCCAAAUCUUUCACUUUGAAAUGUACAAUAAAUUAUUAACUAUAGUCACCCUAUUGUGCUAUCAAACACCAGAUCUUUUUCUGUCUAUCUAAAUGUAUGUUGUAAUCAUUAACCAGCUACUCUUCAUUUCCCACCCUAGCACACCUUUCCCGGGCUUCAGUAUCUAUUGCUCUACUCUCUACCUUCAUGAACUCCCACAUAUAAGUAAUAACAUGUGAUACUUGCCUUUUUGGGCCUGGCUUAUUUCCCUUUGUUUAAUGCCCCCCAGUUCCAUCUAUGUUGCUGUAAAUGACAGAAUUGUAUUAUUUUUCAUGACCGAAUAAUAUUUCAUUGUGUAUAUGUACCACAUUUUGUUUAUCCAUUCAUCUUGAUAGAUACUUAGGUUGAUUUCAUAUCUUGGCUGUUAUGAAUAGUGCUGCAAUAAAAAUAGUGGCACAGAUAUCUCUUUGAUAUGCUGAUUUCUUUUCUUUUAGAUAUAUACUCUGCAGUGGGGUUGCUGGACUAGAACUGUUCAAUACUUUAAUUUUAAUAUUCACUGCAAUAAUUGAUUAUAUGCUGACUAAAAUUCUGAAUUACUAUGAUUACUUCUUAUGAUGCUCCUUAAGGCAUUUGAAAUCCACUGUUUUCAAAGUUUCUGAGGAAAAAUAUAGAUACGUUUUAUAAAACAGACUACUGCAUAUUGAUCAUUUUUAGGGAAAUCUGUGUUAGGUAUGUUGACUUAAAAAGAAGCAUAAGCAAGUCAUAUAAAAGACAAUAGCAAAGGAUUUGAUCAGAACUGGGAGGUAAGACACUGGGUCUAUAAGGAUUCUAUAUCUUGGCUUGCAGAAGGGAGUGCAUAGAUAAGUAGAUGCUAGAUAUAGUGAAUGGGUUUAAUGUUUCGGACCAGUCAUGACCAAUUGGUGGUGGCUGUUCAUACUGCUCUAUAGAAAGAGAUCCUAUACUGAGUCUGGAUUCAUUGGUAAAGGGCAUUGUUAUCAGUUAGUGAUGUUUCCAGUGAUCACAGCUGGAGGACUGUGUAUAGAAGUUUGAGUAUCUGGCCUGCUUAGUUACCAUUUCUGGUUGAGUUAGCACAAUAAGAGGCUCUAGUAAUUAUCACUGAAAAGGAUGGUGCCUGUCCAUGAUCCAGAAUUCCCAAUGAACUAACUGGUAAAAUCCCAGCUAAUGGAACAAGCAUUGCUUUGAAUAAAAACAAGUGUCCAGAAUCUUCUUGAAAGGCCUAGGAUCUCCACUGUUUCAAUGUACACACGUAUUUAUUUAUUUAGUUAGUUAGUUUUGUUUUUAGUGCUGCUUCACCAUGAACACAACAUUGUUGUGUUCUUUUUGUUUUAAAAUUUCUGGUGGCUGAUGAGACCUUGUUCUACAUGAUCAUUUCCACUUUCUCCUAACUUUGAAGCUACAUUUUUUUUUUUGUGGCAACUGUAAAGGUUACUCCUAACCUCAUUCUCUAAAAACUCUGAUUCUUCUUAGAUAUUUGUAUAUAUCCAGUUUUAAUGAGGUAUUGCUUAAAAAUUAUAGAUAUGGAAUUACUAAUCUGACAAUUAGUUUAACUUCUGAUAAUAGCUCUAGUAAGGUAGUGAGAAACAGAGCUAGCUGGAAAGUAAUGUAACACCCAUAUUGAAUUUUUAACAACUUAAUACAUUUUAGGAAAUGAUCCUUCUGAAAGGCAUUAUGGCUUGCUGAGAAAAGCUGUACACUGGGAACCAAGAGAAGUGGGCUUGAUUCCCAGCUCUGCAUCUGACUCACUCUUUGUCCUUGGGCAAGUCACUUAGCCUCUCUCUGUGUCUAUUUCCUGUCUUGUAAAAUCAGGAGAAUAAUGCAUAAAGCCUCCCACCUUACCAAGAUAUGUUGAGGCUGCAUUCUAUAACCACCAGGGGGAAGAAAGAUUCCUUUCUUUCUGGUGGUUAAGUACCAACUUAUUUUUAUUAGCAUCUAGUUAGAUUAAAUUUUGCAAUAAGAGAAUGGAAUUACAAAUAACUUCAAAGAGUCCUUUAAUCCAUGACUUUACACUGGAAUUUUAUUGCAACACACAUUGCUUUGUGUUAAUACACCCAUUGGCUAGCAAGAGGCUUUGAGAGUCUUGUGUGUACAUACAUAUUCAAUGCCUCAAUCUAUUUGAGUACCUACUAUAGAGUCUUGUACUGAGCACAUCAGAACCAAUUCGAAGAGUAGAAGAUAGAAUCCUGGGGAGAAGAGGCUUAAACACCAGAAACAAUUAGAGAACGCCAUCUAGAAAUAUUUAUUCAAAAAUGUUAUUGUCAAGAUUCUAGUUUAGACAAUGAGGAAAUCAAUGUAGUCUGGAAAAUCACAGAGCAAUGCCAUGCAAUAGAUGGAACAAAUGCCUCUGAUUUUAUGACAUCUUCCAUGAUUCCUCCAGUAAAACUCAUCUUCUUUAUUUCCCUCCCGAAUUUGAUAGCUCAUUUUACAUUUUUCCAAUUUUCUCUAUCUUUUAUGGCUUUUUAAAACAUUUUUUUCCUUUUAACUACUACAUAAUCAUGGAUCACACAUUAUAUUUGGUUGUUCUUUUUCUUAAUUCUCCUUUUAUAAUGAAUUGUAGUCCCUCCCUAUUUUUUACAUGAGUUUGACCUUUUGAAAUGAUUCCGUCACUUAUAGAAUAUUCAAUGUUCUGAAUUUGCUCUGACUUUCUCAUUAUUUUAUCUAUCUUUGUCCUCUAUAACUGAUAUUUUCUGUAAACUAGAUAUUAGAUCUAUCGCCUAGACUAGAGUAAGGUUGAGCAUUUCUGGGCGGAAUGUUUUCUGGGUGGUGUUAGGCAUCUGUAUAUUAAUAACUGUGAUGUAAGUUAUCGGUACAUGUACUAGUAGAAUUCAUAGCAUAGAUGGAAAGGCACCUUGAUGUAAUGCUUUGCAGCUUCUGCUUUGCUACCAUACUCAGUGGCAAUAUGGUGUAUCAUUGUAUAAGAAAAGACUGCACUUAUAUAGCACUGUGACCUCUGAUCAAUUACAUUAUCUCUUCAAGUUUAUAUUUUCUUAUCUAUAAAAUGGGGAUAAUGAUACCUAGUAUACAUUAUUCUUUUGAAGUUUUGAGAUAAUACCUGUUUUUUGCACUCAAUUAAAGGAAGUUUAUUAGUAGCAGUAUUAGUAAUAAUGUUUGUUAUAAUAGUAGUAGUCAGUCAUAUAGUCCUGUGUGAUGAAAAUAUUUAAGACUGGCAUGGAUUCCACAAACAGAACAGCAAUGCUAUUCAUAUCAGAAUCCCCACUGUAACAGAUGGAAUUUACCUGUUUGUUUGCUUGUUUGGUUGUUUAAUAUGCCACCAUGUGGUAUGAUUUAAAUGGAGGAUAUCAUCUUUAAAUCCUUUUCAGGAUGAAUCAGGUUAUAAAAAUCCAAUAAAGAAGUUAAAACAUUAUUCAUGGACAAAAGGCUCUCUCAAGACUCUCAUGUUUCUUUGCCCCAUGAUCAUGUUUUGCUUCCUAUACUUGAAUGCAAGGAGAGAAAUGUAUGCGCAGGAUCCAGGAGCCUACACUUGAGCUGUUCCCAGUAAUUUACAAAACACACAUUAGGGUUGAGGUAAUGAGAUUAAGUUUUAAAGUCAGUCUGCUUGUCCUCAAAUGCAGGCUUUAUCACUUGUUAGCUGUAUAACACUGGCCAUGAUACACAAUCUCCCUGAACCUUUGCGCACCUCUUUGCAAAAAAGCUCAAAGGGAUGUUGUGAGUAUAGAACAGAUUUAUAAAACUCCAACUCAAAGUGACUUCCUAACACACACUAAGCAUUAUUGUAGUUUUAUUAUUACAUACAUACUUUUCUGGAUCUCCAGUUUUGCCCACAGUGGGCAGUUAUUAAUGCUUAGAAAUCAGUGAAGUUUAGAAUAGGAGAGAUCAGGGCUGCUGCAAGGUCUGUGCACUGCACAAAGGAACUACAUAUAAAAACUGAAAGGAGGAGUGACAUCCACAUUGCAUUCUAUUUAUCAAACUAUGUGCCCUAAUCCAGGGUUGCAUUUGUCCAAAGUUGCCUUUUUCUAAUUAGCACAAAAGUGCCAUAUAGACUAUUGCUGCCAUAGAUGGAUAUCUAAGCAGAGGGAAUUGCAGGAACAAAAUUAGUGAAGAAAAAGAGAACCAAUUUACAAUAGGUUGUUCAUCAUGAUACAGUAAAUAUAAGAUGAACUCCUGAAGAGUGAGAUAUGUAGGAGAUGUCCUUUAUAAUCUGGUGAACCCAAGGUGGGCUUUAAAAAUAGUUCCUAAAAGAAAUCAUUAACAAUUGUAUGAAUAUAAUUAAUGAACUCCUUUAUUAUCAAAGGAAAGAUCCUUGUUGCAGAAAAUACUUCAGUAUAGAUUCUCAUAUUUUCUCCUUAGAUUAGUCAUUCAAAAUGUAAUUUAUUUUUUCCUCAGAUAGUUUAAAAUGACAUUUUUGCUACAUUAGAACUGAGGGUUUCUCCCACUACUUAUUAACUUAUUGGUGGCCCCUCAAAUCAUGACUGCUCUCUUGCUGCGUGUCCUGUGAGGAUCCACCGCCAUGUUGAAUCUGAAAAUAUCAAGACUAAAUUACUGGCAAUCUGGAAUACUUUUCUGAUCUUGGUAGUAUUAUUUCAGAUAGCUUUUUUUAAAUUUUAUCAGUUAAAAAUAAAGAUUUUUCUGAUUUUCAUUAUAUCUUUUCACCAUGCAGGGCUUUUACAUUUGCCUUAUAAAUAAACAGGUAUGGAGAAAAGGACCAUCUAUUUUACUUUUUAUGCUCCAUAAGUACCACUUUACUUCUUGAAAAAAGAGGAAUUUUUAUUCCAGGAAGAAUGAUGGGCUUGUAUAACAUCAAGUACAUGUUCAAUGCUUCUAAGUGAUAAAUUUACAUAAAGGAUAGUUUGCUUUCUCAUCAGAGUCUCUACAUUAAAGAUUUUCUGUCGGAAAAUCAGAAUGAAGACUAAAAUCAAGGCUUAGGUUUGUCUCUUUUAAUACUACACAUAUCAUUCUAUACAGCUUUUGAAAACAACCAAACCAAGCAUCACUUUUAAAUGUUGACACUGUACUUUGCUGAUGCUAUUAUUUUCUCUUCAGGUAAGGGGCCUGUGAGGAAUGCUUAAUGCAUGUAUUAUUUUCCUCCUCAUUGGGAAAAACUCCCGUUUAAAUAAAAUAAUCCUGAAAUUUAAAACAACAUGUUUUAUUACUUUUGUCUUUUGAAAACCAAACAUGUUACACUUUUGGUUUCAUGCAAAGCAAUUAAAACCAGUAAUUUUAGACAAAUAUGUACAAUGUUAAUCUUGGCCUUCCUUUAACUAAAGGGGCAUAAUUUAUUAGAGUGUGCUGAUAUUUGAAAAUUCUUUAUUUCUGAUAAAUUCAUAGGUAUUCUCAAAAUUAUUUUUAAUAAUUGGAAGAAUAUCAUUUCUUAAAAUAAGCAUUGCUUACAGUAACAACACAGAACUGCUAUCAGAAGUACCCAAGUUAUGUUAUUUUGUUUUUGCUCUUACAUUUUCUUGGUAAAUUCAAGCCUUGUUCUAAUGUUGUAAAAAUAGGAGAAAAAGAAAUUAAAACAUUUCUAGGGUGUUCAAGUGAGUUAACAUCAUAACCACCAAUUGUCAGCAGGCUUUGGGGAGCCAGCAGGGAGCCAUGUUUACCUGACAUAAUGGAUGUGUGAUCACGGAACUCAUUAAGCUAUAACAAUCUUUGGGAAACCGUUGUUCCCCUCCCAAAGUCCACUCUAAAUGUCCUUUUUCCUAGUCCACUGAGGUCCAUAAUGUUUAUAAGGUCAUCAUGUUCUUUUUGUUGUUGUUAGUCUCUUUAAGUUGAUCUUCACAUGUAACAGAAUUCUGUCAAAUGAAAAUUGAGAUAUUUGUCUCUGAAAAAUACAUUUUCAAGUAAGACACCACUUUAGGCUCACUAGAAAAGUUCUUGGAUAAGCAUAAUUCCUGUGACCAAUGGUCCUGAAAUAAUAAGGCACCCCAGCACUUGAAAUACUCAGUUGUCUUUACCUGACGUCAGUUGGGCAAAAUAUACAAGUGAUCUGACUUUAGUGACCUUGGUGAAUAAAUUCUACAGAGCAAAUUUUAGCUGAAGGCUGGAGACAAAAAUAUAACUAGGUCUCAGGUGUGUGGAGCAAUAUCAGCAGUUGUGUGAUCCUGGUGAAUUUCUUUGCCACGAUCACGUGACUUGUGUCUCCCAGAGCUGGCUGUGUGAUGGGGACCCUGACUGCCCUGAUGAUUCAGACGAGUCUUUAGAUACCUGUCCCGAGGAGGUAGAAAUCAAGUGCCCCUUGAAUCACAUUGCUUGCCUUGGUACCAACAAAUGUGUUCAUUUAUCCCAGCUGUGCAAUGGUGUCUUGGACUGCCCAGAUGGGUAUGACGAAGGAGUACAUUGUCAGGAACUGUUAUCCAAUUGCCAACAGCUGAAUUGUCAGUAUAAAUGUACAAUGGUCAGAAAUAGUACAAGAUGUUACUGUGAGGAUGGAUUCGAAAUAACAGAAGAUGGGAGAAGCUGUAAAGAUCAAGAUGAAUGUGCUGUUUAUGGUACAUGCAGCCAGACCUGCAGAAACACACAUGGAUCCUACACUUGCAGUUGUGUGGAAGGCUACCUAAUGCAGCCAGACAACAGAUCUUGCAAGGCUAAAAUUGAACCUACAGAUAGACCACCUAUACUAUUAAUUGCAAAUUUUGAAACAAUUGAGGUUUUCUAUCUUAAUGGAAGUAAAAUGGCAACUCUAAGCUCAGUCAAUGGAAAUGAAAUUCAUACUCUGGAUUUUAUUUAUAAUGAAGAUAUGAUUUGUUGGAUUGAAUCAAGAGAAUCUUCAAAUCAACUCAAAUGUAUCCAGAUAACAAAAGCAGGAGGAUUAACAGAUGAAUGGACAAUCAAUAUUCUUCAAUCCUUCCACAAUGUGCAACAAAUGGCGAUUGACUGGCUCACUCGAAAUCUCUAUUUUGUGGACCAUGUCGGUGACCGGAUCUUUGUUUGUAAUUCCAACGGUUCUGUAUGUGUCACCCUGAUUGAUCUGGAGCUUCACAAUCCUAAAGCAAUAGCAGUAGAUCCAAUAGCAGGAAAACUUUUCUUUACUGACUACGGGAAUGUCGCCAAAGUGGAGAGAUGUGACAUGGAUGGGAUGAACCGAACAAGGAUAAUUGAUUCAAAGACAGAGCAGCCAGCUGCACUGGCACUAGACCUAGUCAACAAAUUGGUUUACUGGGUAGAUCUUUACUUGGACUAUGUGGGAGUAGUGGACUAUCAAGGAAAAAAUAGACACACUGUCAUUCAAGGCAGACAAGUUAGACAUCUUUAUGGUAUAACUGUGUUUGAAGAUUAUUUGUAUGCAACCAAUUCUGAUAACUACAAUAUCGUAAGGAUAAACCGAUUUAAUGGGACUGAUAUUCACUCAUUAAUUAAAAUUGAGAAUGCUUGGGGAAUCCGAAUUUAUCAAAAAAGAACUCAACCAACAGUCAGAAGCCAUGCAUGUGAAGUCGAUCCAUAUGGAAUGCCAGGGGGCUGUUCACACAUCUGUCUACUCAGCAGCAGUUACAAAACUCGGACUUGUCGCUGCAGGACUGGCUUCAACUUGGGAAGUGAUGGCAGGUCAUGCAAAAGACCAAAGAAUGAGUUGUUCCUCUUUUAUGGGAAAGGACGCCCAGGAAUUGUUAGAGGAAUGGACUUGAAUACCAAGAUAGCUGAUGAAUACAUGAUCCCCAUAGAAAAUCUGGUAAACCCUCGUGCUUUAGACUUUCACGCAGAAACCAAUUACAUCUACUUUGCUGACACCACCAGUUUCCUAAUUGGCCGGCAGAAGAUAGAUGGCACAGAGAGAGAAACCAUCCUGAAAGAUGAUCUGGAUAAUGUAGAGGGCAUUGCUGUGGACUGGAUUGGAAAUAAUCUUUACUGGACCAAUGAUGGCCAUAGGAAAACCAUUAAUGUGGCCAGGCUGGAAAAAGCUUCUCAGAGUCGGAAGACUCUUUUAGAGGGUGAAAUGUCUCAUCCCAGAGGAAUUGUGGUGGAUCCAGUUAAUGGUUGGAUGUAUUGGACAGACUGGGAGGAAGAUGAAAUAGAUGACAGCGUGGGAAGGAUUGAGAAGGCCUGGAUGGAUGGAUUCAAUCGGCAGAUUUUUGUGACUUCAAAGAUGCUGUGGCCAAACGGUUUAACUCUGGACUUUCACACCAACACAUUAUACUGGUGUGAUGCCUAUUACGAUCAUAUUGAAAAAGUAUUUUUGAAUGGGACUCACAGGAAGAUUGUUUACAGUGGGAGAGAGUUGAACCACCCUUUCGGACUGUCGCAUCAUGGAAAUUAUGUGUUCUGGACUGAUUAUAUGAAUGGUUCCAUUUUUCAACUAGAUUUGAUAACAAGUGAGGUGACAUUGCUGAGGCAUGAAAGACCACCCCUAUUUGGGCUUCAGAUUUAUGAUCCACGAAAGCAACAAGGUGACAAUAUGUGCCGAGUAAAUAAUGGGGGCUGUAGUACACUUUGCUUGGCUAUCCCAGGAGGCCGGGUGUGUGCUUGUGCCGAUAAUCAACUUUUGGAUGAAAAUGGGACAACUUGCACAUUUAAUCCUGGAGAAGCACUACCUCACAUAUGUAAAGCUGGAGAGUUUCGCUGCAAAAACAGACACUGUAUCCAAGCUCGGUGGAAAUGUGAUGGCGACGAUGACUGCCUAGACGGAAGCGAUGAGGAUUCAGUAAACUGCUUCAAUCAUAGCUGUCCUGAUGAUCAGUUUAAAUGCCAGAAUAAUCGCUGCAUCCCCAAGAGAUGGCUUUGUGAUGGAGCUAAUGACUGUGGGAGCAAUGAAGAUGAAUCCAAUCAAACUUGCACAGCCAGAACAUGCCAGGUAGACCAGUUUUCUUGCGGAAAUGGGCGUUGCAUUCCCAGAGCAUGGCUGUGUGACAGGGAAGACGACUGUGGUGACCAGACAGAUGAAAUGGCAUCUUGUGAAUUCCCAACUUGUGAGCCACUAACCCAAUUCGUAUGCAAAAGUGGAAGAUGCAUUAGCAGCAAAUGGCACUGCGACUCUGAUGACGACUGUGGGGACGGGAGUGAUGAGGUGGGCUGUGUUCACUCUUGCUUUGAUAAUCAGUUCAGAUGUUCCAGUGGCAGAUGCAUCCCAGGCCACUGGGCCUGUGAUGGUGACAAUGACUGUGGGGACUUCAGUGAUGAAGCCCAGAUCAAUUGUACUAAAGAAGAGAUUCAUUCUCCUGCUGGUUGUAACGGAAAUGAAUUUCAGUGCCACCCUGAUGGUAAUUGCGUUCCUGAUUUGUGGCGCUGUGAUGGAGAAAAAGACUGUGAAGAUGGUAGUGAUGAAAAAGGUUGCAAUGGUACCAUACGAUUGUGUGACCACAAAACCAAGUUUUCCUGUUGGAGUACAGGGAGAUGCAUCAACAAAGCAUGGGUGUGUGAUGGAGAUAUUGAUUGCGAAGAUCAGUCAGAUGAAGAUGACUGUGACAGUUUCUUGUGUGGACCACCCAAGCAUCCUUGUGCUAAUGACACCUCAGUCUGCCUGCAGCCAGAGAAACUCUGCAAUGGGAAAAAGGAUUGUCCUGAUGGCUCUGAUGAAGGCUAUCUCUGUGAUGAGUGUUCGCUGAACAAUGGAGGCUGUAGCAACCACUGUUCUGUUGUUCCUGGAAGAGGAAUUGUCUGUUCCUGCCCUGAAGGACUUCAACUCAACAAAGACAAUAAAACAUGUGAAAUUGUGGAUUAUUGUAGCAAUCAUCUAAAGUGCAGCCAAGUAUGUGAGCAGCACAAGCACACAGUCAAGUGCUCAUGUUAUGAAGGUUGGAAGCUGGAUGUAGACGGUGAAAGUUGUACAAGUGUUGAUCCUUUUGAAGCAUUCAUCAUCUUUUCUAUUCGUCAUGAGAUCAGAAGGAUUGAUCUUCACAAAAGAGACUAUAGUCUACUUGUUCCUGGAUUGAGAAACACAAUAGCACUUGAUUUUCACUUCAAUCAAAGUUUACUUUAUUGGACAGAUGUUGUAGAAGACAGAAUAUACCGGGGAAAGCUUUCUGAAAGUGGAGGUGUCAGUGCCAUUGAAGUGGUUGUGGAGCAUGGCCUGGCUACUCCAGAAGGCCUGACAGUCGACUGGAUAGCAGGAAACAUAUACUGGAUAGACAGCAAUCUGGACCAAAUCGAAGUGGCCAAACUAGAUGGCUCCCUAAGAACUACACUAAUAGCAGGAGCCAUGGAACACCCCAGGGCCAUUGCUUUGGACCCAAGAUAUGGAAUUCUUUUCUGGACAGACUGGGAUGCAAAUUUUCCUCGCAUUGAAUCUGCCUCUAUGAGUGGUGCUGGGAGAAAAACCAUCUAUAAAGACAUGAAAACUGGGGCUUGGCCUAAUGGACUAACUGUGGACCACUUUGAGAAAAGGAUAGUGUGGACAGACGCCAGGUCAGAUGCUAUUUAUUCAGCCCUCUAUGAUGGAACAAACAUGAUAGAAAUCAUCCGAGGUCAUGAAUACCUUUCCCAUCCCUUUGCUGUGUCUCUAUAUGGGAGUGAAGUCUACUGGACAGACUGGAGGACCAACACAUUGUCCAAAGCCAAUAAGUGGACAGGGCAGAAUGUCAGUGUGAUUCAGAAAACCAGUGCACAGCCAUUUGACCUUCAGAUAUACCAUCCCAGUCGCCAGCCACAGGCUCCCAAUCCUUGUGCAGCUAAUGAUGGCAAAGGCCCCUGCUCUCACAUGUGUCUAAUCAAUCACAAUAGGAGUGCUGCCUGUGCGUGCCCCCACUUGAUGAAGCUUUCUUCAGACAAGAAGACCUGCUAUGAAAUGAAAAAAUUUCUUCUUUAUGCAAGACGUUCUGAAAUCAGAGGAGUGGAUAUUGACAAUCCAUACUUUAACUUCAUCACGGCAUUUACAGUCCCUGAUAUUGAUGACGUUACUGUGAUAGACUUCGAUGCAUCUGAGGAACGUUUAUACUGGACAGAUAUUAAAACACAAACCAUUAAACGAGCUUUUAUUAACGGAACUGGGUUAGAAACUGUUAUUUCAAGAGAUAUUCAGAGUAUCAGAGGGCUAGCAGUGGAUUGGGUGUCACGUAAUUUAUACUGGAUUAGCUCAGAAUUUGAUGAAACGCAAAUUAAUGUGGCAAGGCUAGAUGGCUCUUUGAAAACCUCAAUUAUCCAUGGAAUCGAUAAGCCACAGUGUCUUGCAGCUCACCCAGUCAGGGGAAAACUCUACUGGACCGAUGGAAACACAAUUAACAUGGCAAAUAUGGAUGGCAGUAAUAGCAAGAUUCUGUUUCAGAAUCAGAAGGAGCCAGUUGGUCUAUCGAUAGACUAUGUGGAAAACAAGCUUUAUUGGAUCAGUUCAGGGAAUGGAACCAUAAAUAGAUGCAACCUGGAUGGUGGUAAUUUAGAAGUAAUCGAGUCAAUGAAAGAAGAAUUAACAAAAGCUACAGCCCUAACCAUCAUGGAUAAGAAACUGUGGUGGGCAGACCAAAACUUAGCCCAGCUAGGAACCUGCAGCAAAAGAGACGGAAGAAACCCCACCAUCCUACGGAAUAAGACUUCUGGGGUAGUUCAUAUGAAAGUCUAUGAUAAAGAAGCACAGCAAGGCAGCAAUUCCUGCCAACUAAACAAUGGUGGAUGCUCUCAACUUUGUUUACCAACAUCUGAAACUACAAGGACUUGUAUGUGUACAGUGGGAUAUUAUCUCCAAAAGAACCGUAUGUCAUGUCAAGGUAUAGAAUCAUUUCUUAUGUACUCUGUUCAUGAAGGAAUCAGGGGAAUACCUCUUGAACCAAGUGACAAAAUGGAUGCUUUGAUGCCUAUAUCAGGAACUUCAUUUGCCGUGGGAAUAGAUUUCCAUGCAGAAAAUGAUACCAUCUACUGGACAGACAUGGGCUUCAAUAAAAUUAGCAGAGCUAAAAGAGAUCAGACUUGGAAAGAAGAUAUCAUUACCAAUGGCUUGGGAAGAGUGGAAGGGAUAGCUGUUGACUGGAUUGCUGGUAACAUAUAUUGGACAGAUCAUGGUUUCAACUUAAUUGAAGUUGCAAGACUCAAUGGUUCUUUCCGUUAUGUAAUUAUUUCCCAAGGCCUGGAUCAACCAAGAUCUAUAGCUGUGCACCCAGAGAAAGGCCUCUUGUUCUGGACUGAAUGGGGACAAAUGCCCUGUAUUGGAAAGGCUCGCUUGGAUGGCUCAGAGAAGGUUGUCCUUGUAAGCAUGGGAAUAGCAUGGCCGAAUGGCAUCUCCAUCGACUAUGAGGAAAAUAAAUUGUACUGGUGUGAUGCUCGCACAGACAAGAUAGAGAGAAUCGACCUUGAGACUGGAGGGAAUCGCGAGAUGGUGCUGUCAGGAAGCAAUGUGGAUAUGUUUUCAGUUGCAGUCUUUGGGGCUUACAUCUACUGGUCUGACAGAGCACAUGCAAACGGGUCUGUCAGAAGGGGCCACAAGAAUGAUGCCACAGAAACGAUAACCAUGAGAACCGGCCUUGGAGUCAACCUGAAGGAGGUUAAAAUAUUUAACCGAGUAAGAGAGAAAGGGACCAAUGUUUGUGCCAGGGACAAUGGUGGCUGUAAGCAACUCUGUCUUUAUCGAGGAAAUUCCCGGAGAACUUGUGCUUGUGCCCAUGGAUAUUUGGCAGAAGAUGGAGUUACUUGCCUGAGGCAUGAAGGCUAUUUACUGUAUUCAGGAAGAACAAUAUUAAAAAGUAUACAUCUUUCUGAUGAAACCAAUUUAAAUUCCCCAAUAAGGCCAUAUGAGAAUCCACGUUAUUUCAAGAAUGUCAUAGCCUUGGCUUUUGACUAUAAUCAAAGAAGAAAAGGUACCAACCGAAUCUUUUACAGUGAUGCACACUUUGGAAAUAUACAGCUUAUUAAAGACAACUGGGAAGACAGACAAGUAAUUGUUGAAAAUGUGGGUUCUGUGGAAGGACUUGCCUAUCACAGAGCCUGGGAUACACUGUACUGGACAAGCUCUACCACCUCAUCCAUCACCAGACACACUGUGGACCAGACUCGGCCUGGAGCAUUUGACAGGGAAGCUGUCAUCACCAUGUCAGAAGAUGACCAUCCACAUGUGCUAGCCUUGGAUGAAUGUCAAAAUUUAAUGUUUUGGACCAACUGGAAUGAACAACAUCCAAGUAUCAUGAGAUCUACUCUGACUGGGAAAAAUGCUCAAGUGGUGGUCAGUACAGACAUACUCACUCCAAAUGGACUUACUAUCGACUACCGUGCAGAGAAGCUGUAUUUCUCAGAUGGCAGUCUAGGAAAAAUUGAAAGGUGUGAAUACGAUGGAUCCCAGAGACAUGUGAUAGUUAAAUCUGGGCCAGGGACUUUCCUCAGUUUGGCUGUUUAUGACAAUUAUAUAUUCUGGUCGGACUGGGGAAGAAGAGCUAUACUGCGGUCCAACAAGUACACAGGAGGAGAUACAAAAAUUCUUCGUUCCGAUAUUCCACAUCAGCCAAUGGGAAUCAUAGCUGUUGCCAAUGACACCAAUAGCUGUGAACUUUCUCCAUGUGCAUUAUUGAAUGGAGGCUGCCAUGACUUGUGCCUUUUAACUCCCAAUGGGAGAGUGAAUUGUUCCUGCAGAGGGGACCGAAUAUUGCUAGAGGACAACAGAUGUGUGACUAAAAAUUCCUCCUGCAACGCUUAUUCGGAGUUUGAAUGUGGAAAUGGUGAGUGCAUUGACUACCAGCUCACCUGUGAUGGCAUUCCUCACUGUAAAGAUAAAUCAGAUGAAAAACUGCUCUACUGUGAAAACAGAAGCUGUCGAAGAGGCUUCAAGCCAUGCUAUAAUCGCCGCUGCAUUCCUCAUGGCAAGUUAUGUGAUGGAGAAAAUGACUGCGGAGACAACUCUGAUGAAUUAGAUUGUAAAGUUUCAACCUGUGCCACGGUUGAGUUCCGCUGUGCAGAUGGGACUUGUAUUCCAAGAUCAGCACGAUGCAACCAGAACAUAGAUUGUGCAGAUGCUUCAGAUGAAAAGAACUGCAAUAACACAGACUGCACACAUUUCUAUAAGCUUGGAGUGAAAACCACAGGGUUCAUAAGAUGUAAUUCUACCUCACUGUGUGUUCUGCCAACCUGGAUAUGCGACGGGUCUAAUGACUGUGGAGACUAUUCAGAUGAAUUAAAGUGCCCAGUUCAAAACAAACACAAAUGUGAAGAAAAUUAUUUUAGUUGUCCUAGUGGAAGAUGCAUUUUGAAUACCUGGAUAUGCGAUGGUCAGAAAGAUUGUGAGGAUGGACGUGAUGAAUUCCACUGUGAUUCUUCUUGCUCUUGGAACCAAUUUGCUUGUUCCGCACAAAAAUGUAUUUCUAAGCAUUGGAUUUGUGAUGGAGAAGAUGACUGUGGGGAUGGGUUAGAUGAAAGUGACAGCAUUUGUGGUGCCAUAACCUGUGCUGCUGACAUGUUCAGCUGCCAGGGCUCUCGUGCCUGCGUGCCCCGACAUUGGCUUUGUGAUGGUGAAAGGGACUGUCCAGAUGGAAGCGAUGAGCUUUCCACAGCAGGCUGCGCUCCCAAUAAUACAUGUGAUGAAAAUGCUUUCAUGUGCCAUAAUAAAGUAUGCAUUCCCAAGCAAUUUGUUUGUGACCAUGAUGACGACUGUGGAGAUGGCUCUGAUGAGUCACCGCAGUGUGGAUAUCGACAGUGUGGUACAGAAGAAUUUAGUUGUGCUGAUGGGCGGUGUCUUCUAAAUACUCAAUGGCAGUGUGAUGGAGACUUUGACUGUCCUGACCAUUCUGAUGAAGCACCUUUAAACCCAAAGUGUAAAAGUGCAGAACAGUCAUGCAACAGUUCAUUUUUUAUGUGCAAAAAUGGCAGGUGCAUUCCCAGUGGAGGUCUUUGCGACAAUAAGGAUGACUGUGGCGAUGGUUCAGAUGAGAGAAACUGCCAUAUAAAUGAAUGUUUGAGUAAGAAAGUCAGUGGAUGUUCUCAAGACUGUCAAGACCUUCCGGUCAGUUAUAAGUGCAAAUGCUGGCCUGGAUUCCAACUGAAGGAUGACGGCAAAACAUGUGUAGACAUUGAUGAAUGCUCUUCAGGCUUUCCCUGUAGCCAGCAAUGCAUCAAUACAUACGGGACUUACAAGUGCCUCUGUACAGAUGGGUAUGAAAUACAACCUGAUAACCCAAAUGGCUGCAAAUCGCUCUCAGAUGAAGAACCUUUUUUAAUUCUUGCUGAUCAUCAUGAGAUAAGGAAAAUUAGCACUGAUGGCUCCAACUACACACUUUUAAAACAGGGAUUAAACAAUGUUAUUGCUAUAGACUUUGAUUACAGAGAAGAAUUCAUCUAUUGGAUCGAUUCUAGCCGACCCAAUGGCAGUCGCAUAAAUAGAAUGUGUUUAAAUGGAAGUGACAUUAAGGUAGUUCAUAACACAGCGGUCCCCAAUGCACUUGCUGUCGAUUGGAUUGGAAAAAACCUCUAUUGGUCUGACACAGAAAAAAGAAUCAUUGAAGUAUCCAAACUCAAUGGCUUGUACCCUACUAUACUCGUUAGCAAAAGGCUGAAGUUUCCCAGAGACUUGUCUUUAGAUCCUCAAGCUGGAUAUUUGUAUUGGAUUGACUGCUGCGAGUAUCCUCAUAUUGGCCGUGUUGGAAUGGAUGGAACCAAUCAGAGUGUUGUCAUAGAAACCAAGAUUUCUAGACCUAUGGCACUAACAAUAGAUUAUGUUAAUCGUAGACUCUACUGGGCCGAUGAAAAUCACAUUGAAUUUAGCAACAUGGAUGGAUCUCAUAGACACAAAGUCCCUAAUCAAGAUAUUCCAGGGGUGAUUGCACUAACAUUGUUUGAAGACUACAUCUACUGGACUGAUGGGAAAACCAAGUCACUCAGCCGUGCCCAUAAAACAUCGGGAGCAGACAGACUCUCACUGAUUUACUCAUGGCAUGCCAUCACAGAUAUCCAGGUGUAUCAUUCUUAUAGACAACCUGAUGUCUCCAAACAUCUCUGCAUGAUAAAUAAUGGUGGUUGCAGUCAUUUGUGCCUUUUAGCCCCUGGAAAAACCCACACUUGUGCAUGUCCCACUAACUUCUAUCUGGCAGCUGAUAAUAGGACUUGCUUAUCCAACUGCACAGCCAGCCAGUUUCGUUGCAAAACUGACAAAUGUAUUCCAUUCUGGUGGAAAUGUGACACCGUGGAUGACUGUGGUGAUGGAUCUGAUGAACCUGAUGACUGUCCUGAAUUUAGAUGUCAGCCAGGCCGAUUUCAGUGUGGGACUGGACUCUGUGCUCUACCAGCUUUCAUCUGUGAUGGAGAGAAUGAUUGUGGAGACAAUUCUGAUGAACUCAACUGUGACACACAUGUCUGCCUGUCAGGUCAAUUCAAAUGUACCAAGAACCAGAAAUGUAUCCCAGUAAACUUAAGAUGUAAUGGGCAAGAUGACUGUGGUGAUGAGGAAGAUGAAAGAGACUGUCCUGAAAACAGCUGUUCUCCAGACUAUUUCCAGUGUAAGACUACGAAGCAUUGCAUUUCCAAGCUGUGGGUUUGUGACGAGGAUCCAGACUGUGCAGAUGCAUCAGACGAGGCCAACUGCGAUAAAAAGACUUGUGGACCUCAUGAAUUCCAGUGUAAAAACAACAACUGUAUUCCCGAUCACUGGCGGUGUGAUAGCCAAAAUGACUGCAGUGAUAAUUCAGAUGAAGAAAACUGUAAGCCACAGACAUGUACAUUGAAAGAUUUCCUCUGUGCCAAUGGGGACUGUGUUUCUUCAAGGUUUUGGUGUGAUGGAGAUUUUGACUGUGCAGAUGGCUCUGAUGAGAGAAAUUGUGAGACAAGUUGUUCCAAAGAUCAGUUCCGGUGUUCCAAUGGUCAGUGUAUACCAGCAAAAUGGAAAUGUGAUGGCCAUGAAGACUGCAAAUAUGGGGAAGAUGAGAAAAGCUGUGAGCCAGCUUCUCCUACUUGCUCAUCACGUGAAUAUAUAUGUGCCAGUGAUGGAUGUAUUUCAGCAUCUUUGAAAUGUAAUGGAGAAUAUGAUUGUGCUGAUGGUUCAGAUGAGAUGGACUGUGUGACUGAAUGUAAGGAAGAUCAGUUUCGGUGCAAAAAUAAAGCCCACUGUAUUCCAAUUAGAUGGCUGUGUGAUGGAAUUCAUGACUGUGUGGAUGGCAGUGAUGAAGAGAACUGUGAAAGAGGAGGAAAUAUAUGUAGAGCUGAUGAGUUCCUUUGCAAUAAUUCUCUCUGCAAACUACAUUUCUGGGUGUGUGAUGGAGAGGACGACUGUGGAGACAACUCUGAUGAAGCCCCUGAUAUGUGUGUCAAAUUUCUUUGUCCAUCCACGAGACCUCACAGAUGCAGAAAUAACAGAAUAUGCCUACAGUCGGAGCAAAUGUGCAAUGGGAUUGAUGAAUGCGGUGACAAUUCAGAUGAAGAUCACUGUGGUGGUAAGCUGACAUAUAAAGCAAGGCCUUGUAAAAAGGAUGAGUUUGCUUGUAGUAAUAAAAAAUGCAUCCCUAUGGAUCUCCAGUGUGAUCGACUUGAUGACUGCGGAGAUGGUUCAGAUGAGCAAGGAUGCAGAAUAGCUCCUACUGAAUAUACCUGUGAAGAUAAUGUGAAUCCAUGUGGAGAUGAUGCAUAUUGUAAUCAAAUAAAAACAUCUGUUUUCUGUCGCUGUAAGCCUGGAUUUCAGAGAAACAUGAAAAACAGACAAUGUGAAGACCUUAAUGAAUGUUUGGUGUUUGGCACAUGUUCCCAUCAAUGUAUAAAUGUGGAAGGAUCAUAUAAAUGUGUGUGUGACCAGAAUUUUCAAGAAAGAAAUAACACCUGCAUAGCAGAAGGCUCUGAAGAUCAAGUUCUCUACAUUGCUAAUGACACUGAUAUCCUGGGUUUUAUAUAUCCAUUCAACUACAGUGGCGAUCAUCAACAAAUUUCUCAUAUUGAACAUAAUUCAAGAAUAACAGGGAUGGAUGUAUAUUAUCAAAGAGAUAUGAUUAUUUGGAGUACUCAGUUUAAUCCAGGCGGAAUUUUCUACAAAAGGAUCCAUGGCAGAGAAAAAAGGCAAGCAAACAGUGGCUUGAUUUGUCCUGAAUUUAAAAGGCCCAGGGACAUUGCAGUUGACUGGGUGGCUGGAAACAUUUACUGGACUGAUCAUUCUAGAAUGCAUUGGUUCAGUUACUACACUACUCACUGGACCAGUCUGAGGUACUCUAUCAACGUAGGGCAGCUGAAUGGCCCCAACUGCACCAGACUCUUAACAAAUAUGGCUGGAGAACCCUAUGCUAUUGCAGUAAAUCCUAAAAGAGGGAUGAUGUACUGGACUGUUGUUGGGGAUCAUUCCCAUAUAGAAGAAGCAGCCAUGGAUGGUACACUGAGAAGGAUUUUAGUACAAAAGAACUUACAGAGACCCACAGGUUUGGCUGUGGAUUAUUUUAGUGAACGCAUAUAUUGGGCUGACUUUGAGCUCUCCAUCAUUGGCAGUGUUCUGUAUGAUGGCUCUAAUUCAGUAGUCUCUGUCAGCAGCAAACAAGGUUUAUUACAUCCACAUAGGAUCGAUAUCUUUGAAGAUUAUAUAUAUGGAGCAGGACCUAAAAAUGGUGUAUUUCGAGUUCAAAAAUUUGGCCAUGGUUCAGUAGAGUACUUAGCUUUAAAUAUUGAUAAAACAAAAGGUGUUUUGAUAUCUCAUCGUUAUAAACAACUAGAUUUACCCAAUCCAUGCUUGGAUUUAGCAUGCGAAUUUCUUUGCUUGCUAAAUCCUUCUGGGGCCACUUGUGUGUGUCCAGAAGGAAAAUAUUUGAUUAAUGGCACCUGCAAUGAUGACAGCCUGUUAGAUGAUUCAUGUAAGUUAACUUGUGAAAAUGGAGGAAGAUGCAUUUUAAAUGAGAAAGGUGAUUUGAGGUGUCACUGUUGGCCCAGUUAUUCAGGAGAAAGAUGUGAAGUCAACCACUGUAGCAACUACUGCCAGAAUGGAGGAACUUGCGUACCAUCAGUUCUAGGGAGACCCACCUGCAGCUGUGCACUGGGUUUCACUGGGCCAAACUGUGGUAAGACAGUCUGUGAGGAUUUUUGUCAAAAUGGAGGAACCUGCAUUGUGACUGCUGGAAACCAGCCUUACUGCCACUGCCAGCCGGAAUACACCGGAGACAGAUGUCAGUACUACGUGUGCCACCACUAUUGUGUGAAUUCUGAAUCAUGUACCAUUGGGGAUGAUGGAAGUGUUGAAUGUGUCUGUCCAACGCGCUAUGAAGGACCAAAAUGUGAGGUUGACAAGUGUGUAAGGUGCCAUGGGGGGCACUGCAUUAUAAAUAAAGACAGUGAAGAUAUAUUUUGCAACUGCACUAAUGGAAAGAUUGCCUCUAGCUGUCAGUUAUGUGAUGGCUACUGUUACAAUGGUGGCACAUGCCAGCUGGACCCCGAGACAAAUGUACCUGUGUGUCUAUGCUCCACCAACUGGUCAGGCACACAGUGUGAAAGGCCAGCCCCAAAGAGCAGCAAGUCUGAUCAUAUCAGCACAAGAAGCAUUGCCAUCAUUGUGCCUCUCGUCCUCUUGGUGACUUUGAUAACCACCUUAGUAAUUGGUUUAGUGCUUUGUAAAAGAAAAAGAAGGACAAAAACAAUUAGAAGACAACCUAUUAUCAAUGGAGGAAUAAAUGUAGAAAUUGGCAAUCCAUCUUAUAACAUGUAUGAGGUAGAUCAUGAUCACAACGAUGGAGGUCUUUUAGAUCCUGGCUUUAUGAUAGACCCAACAAAGGCCAGGUACAUAGGGGGAGGACCCAGUGCUUUCAAGCUUCCACACACAGCGCCGCCCAUCUACCUAAACUCUGAUUUGAAAGGACCACUAACUGCUGGGCCAACAAAUUACUCCAAUCCGGUAUAUGCAAAAUUAUAUAUGGAUGGGCAAAACUGUCGAAACUCCUUAGGAAGUGUUGAUGAAAGGAAAGAACUGCUUCCAAAGAAAAUAGAAAUUGGUAUAAGAGAGACAGUGGCAUAAUCAGUGAUAUCUUUUAUAUGCUGUAUAAAUGUAUAAAAUAUAAGGAUUACUUUUGUAUGUUCCAACAGUAUUAUACUUGUUUUGGCAUCAGCAUUACCUCUUUCUUUAUCUUUUUCCUGGUUAAUUGUUUUCUGAGUUUUUUGGGUUUUAUUUUUUGCUGAUGACUAUUGAUUGACCAUUUGUAUGGUAUUUUUAUGAAAAAGAACUGCACUACAGUACAAUUUACAACAAUGCUGCUGAUAUGACACACCUUUGAAUUUGUUAAAAUUAAAAACAACGUAUUCCUUUGUAGUGUGAAUAUGAGCAAUCUAUUUUAUAUGAACUUUUUUGGUUGUACUUAAUCAACGAGGAGAAUCUCUGCACUUUUCCAUUAUACGGUUUGAAGGCUGUAAUACAGUGUCAUAUUAUUUUUCUGUUUAAAUUGAUGGAAAAAUGAUUGAAUGGUCAACUCUCUUCUUUGUGCCCAUAAAGAUCGAUUCAGACUCUGCUGAAAAUAUAUAGCUCUCACAAGUUCAGCAUCACCUGCUUUGAAAUUAGCCUUAGAUUGCCAACCAAUAGAUGAGAAUUUUGAGGAAAAAAAUUAAAAAUAUGUAAAAUUAAUAAUUUGCAUGAACACAGAUGACUACAUUUUCCAAAACUUAGUGGACUCUAUGUGAUGUACUAAAUGUAUACACCUUGUAAGCAAUAGUUAUAUUUAGGUGGUAGAACAUAGCAAAAAUAUAACCGAAAGUUGGCCGACUGCACUUGCUAUGGAAUAAGACCUUUUAUUCUCCCUCAGUCUCGAGAUAAAUAGCCAGCCUAGAGCACAACAGGGCAUUGGGUACUUGCAUCUUAGGUAUUUCUUCCCAGUCACAUCCAUUUUGUGGAAGAUUAACCCAACCCCUUACACUACACUGAACACUAAAGAAUAAUAUAUAAGCACACAAAUUGGUGACAGAAUUUCAAUUACGUGAACGCAUCCUCUUUGCUAGGUCAAAAAACAAAGGGCAAAGCAGACAUUUUAGUAUACAGAGUGAUUGGCAAAUAUUUUCAAGAUUUAAUAUGAGCAACCCAUUAUUUGCCCUAUCCAAAAUAUAUUCAAGGGCCUUCCAAGUUGUAGAAGAACAAUGAUCUUCCCAUAAUCAAAAGUGGAGAGUCGAAAUGCUGUGCCAGUUGCUCUGGUAUUCAGGUUUCUCUGGGUUUUACAGAACGCAUGGACCCCAUUCACGUUUGGUUUGUUUAUCUUCAAAUUUGAGUUGAAACGAGUGCGAUUUAUUUAAGUUGUAUAUAAAAAUAAAAGGAUAGCAUUUUUAUACAAAUAUCUUUAAAGGCACAAAAGAUUUAUUCACAAGUUUUGGAGGGCUUUUUGUUCCUCUGAUAGACAUGACUGACUUUUAGCUGUCAUAAUGUAUUAACCUAACAGAUGAAAUAUGUUAAAUAUGUGGUUGCUCUUUAUCCCUUUGUACAAGCAUUAAAAAAACUGCUGUUUUAUAAGAAGACUUUUUGUUGUACUAUGUGCAUGCAUACUACCUAUUUCUAAACUUUGCCAUAUUGAGGCCUUUAUAAACUAUUGAUUUAUGUAAUACUAGUGCAAUUUUGCUUGAACAAUGUUAUGCAUAUCAUAAACUUUUUCAGGUUCUUGUUUAAGUACAUUUUUUAAAUUGAACAGUAUUUUUCAUUUUGGUUAUAAUAUAGUCAUUUUGCCUAUGUUUCUACAAUGAAGUGUUAAAUACUUUAUAAAAAAUUGUUGACUGACUUAUUUAAAUGAAAUUCUACAUAUUUAA